AAGUGAGAGAGCGCGAGCUCUACCUACCGACAGUGAGGAGCGCCGCCGCCGCCGCCGCCGCCCGCUCGCCGCCCGCCGCCGCCGCCGCCCGCGCCCCAGCCCCGGGAGCUCUGCUGAUCCGGCCGAGCUCAGCACCGAGGCGCCCCCCAACCUGCCCAGCCCCCAGCCCACCAGCCCAGCCCAGUCCCGGGGAGCCAGCUGGCCUGGGGUUCGGUCCCGGGGGGAGGGGAGUUUCGGGGGUACUGGGCGGGGUACUCGUGAGCCAGAGGGGAGGGGGCCGCGGGUUUUCAUGUACCCAGCAUGAGCUCCUACUUCGUCAACCCCCUGUUCUCCAAAUACAAAGCCGGCGAGUCCCUGGAACCGGCCUAUUACGACUGCCGGUUCCCUCAGAGCGUGGGCAGGAGCCAUGCGCUGGUGUACGGGCCCGGCGGCUCGGCGCCCGGCUUCCAGCACGCUUCGCACCACGUUCAAGACUUCUUCCACCACGGCACCUCCGGCAUCUCCAACUCAGGCUACCAGCAGAACCCGUGCUCGCUUAGCUGCCACGGAGACGCCUCCAAAUUCUAUGGCUACGAGGCGCUCCCCAGACAGUCCCUUUAUGGGGCUCAGCAAGAGGCGAGCGUGGUGCAAUAUCCCGACUGUAAAUCCUCCGCCAACACUAACAGUAGCGAAGGACAAGGCCACUUAAAUCAAAACUCGUCUCCCAGCCUCAUGUUUCCAUGGAUGAGACCCCACGCUCCGGGGAGGCGCAGUGGACGGCAAACUUACAGCCGGUAUCAGACCUUGGAACUAGAAAAGGAGUUUCUCUUUAAUCCUUAUUUGACACGAAAACGUCGGAUUGAAGUCUCUCAUGCCCUGGGACUGACCGAGAGACAAGUGAAGAUCUGGUUCCAGAACCGAAGGAUGAAGUGGAAAAAGGAGAACAACAAGGAUAAACUGCCGGGAGCCCGAGAUGAGGAGAAGGUGGAGGAAGAAGGAAAUGAGGAAGAGGAGAAAGAAGAGGAGGAAAAGGAAGAAAACAAGGACUAAGCAAAAAAGAAAGACCCCCCCCCCCUUAGCAACUCCCUUGAAGUUUCGUUUUAUGGUAGCAGAUAAAUUGAGAAGUUUACGACUGUCAUUUGCUUUUAUAGAGAAUAGAAUGACACUCACAACUCUAACUACCUGUCAGAUACUUGCAGCUCUGGUUUUAUUACCUUUGGACUUCCCCCACUCUUUAUUUGUUUGGGGGCUGGAGGGGGGAGACGGAGAAACAGUGAAAAGUUCGGACUCUCUGUCUCACUCCUUGCCCCACACACACUUGUCCCUGCCCCCACCCUUCUGAGUCCUUCCUGGAUUUUAAGGUCUGAGACCUGGCCUCCGUGCUCCUCGGUCUGUCUCUCACCACACUCCCACCUCCCUGCUUCUCUGGUAUUUAUUUUAGAGGGGAGCCCCCUCGAAAUGCAGAAAAGGACUUGUGGUUUUGUUUUUAUGCUAAGGCUAGUGUACUAGAUGUACUUUUUCUAAAAAGGAAAGGACAGAAAAAAAUGAAGAAAGGAAAGGAAGACAAAUGUAAAGAAAUAAGGAAAAAAGCAAGGAAUAUCCCCUCCCCCUCCCCCUCCCCCUCCCCAGGGCUCCCUGCUUAGAAAAACCCCCUUGACUUUCUCUAGGAACCUGAUGGAAACCUGAAGGAGAUGUGGGUCUUUCCCCUCCCCCCAUUUCCAGAAGGGUAGAUAGGAGCCUGCAGUCGCCUCUAAAAUCCUACCUAACCAUCCCAUGGUCACUCGGGCCCAUGCCUUCCUCUCCUUCGCUGUUUGAUUUCUAUUCUGUUGGGCCCGCCUUCCUCUGAGCUGCAUUAGUGUUAGUGCUCAGAAAUCACCAUAAUCACGAAAAUAAUAAUAAUAAAUCUUUAACAUACUACCUAAAGGGAACCUGCAAUAAUCUUGAAAAAGAAAAAGAGAAAAAUUUUAAAAUCCUGCUAUAGGAGAAAAAAAGAGAAAAAAAUAAAAAUCAAAAAAAAAAAAAAGAAAGAAAGAAACCUCCAGCGUAUUUUAUCACUACCUAUAGAAAGAAAUCCUGCUUUGAGAGUAUUUGUAAUGCGGUUUUGUUGUCGUUUGUUGCUGCUUAUUUCACUAAGAAAACCCAACAACUGAGACUGCCUAGCCCGCCGGUCCUGUGCGCUUUUAUUGUGCUUCUAACCCCAGUAGAGUAGAACUAAAUUGCACUGAAUGUAUAGUUAACUCUGUCUUGAAUUCUCUGUUUAUGCAAUGUGCUCGAAAGAAAAAAAUGUUAAAAAUAUAUCUAUAAUAAUAAUUUUUUGUCAUUUGUCUUUAUGUCCAGCUAUGAAUGUAGAUUUUGUGUCCCGACAGCCCUGUUCCUGGUCCAAGUACUUUGUAUUGUAUACGUGAGUCAUAAUAAUAAAAAGAAGAAGAAAAAUAAUA